ACUUCUGCUGCCGCUAGGGGUAGCGGCGGCGGCGGCGGCUGCGGCUCGGGAGCGCGGCUGCUUUGAGGGCUCGGGAACCUUACAGAGUGGGGACGUGGGGAGGCUAGAGGGUGAGAAAGCUGGCGGGAGAGUAGGGCGGCGCUGGAGGAGGGCGGUGCGUGGCUGACUCAUCCUCUGGAAGAUCAGACUGACAGAGACACACACUAGCCCGCCCCGCCCGCCCGCGCCGCUCCUCCUCAGCCGGGAGGCGCCCGCCCGCACCGACCGCCCGCCCUCUCCGGGCGCUGUCCGGGCCCGGCCGUCUCAGAGAAAGUUUUUCCCAUCGGAGGGGCGGGAGCCGCCGCGGGCCUUUUGGAAAGGAAGUGGGGACGGAACAGGAGGCGAGAGCCGCGCGGGCCCGCGGAGUGCAUGGUGCCCGGCGCCUCGGCUGCCUGGCAGGAGGACCUCGGGGCGGGGUCGAGCUGAGCCCAGCUCCUUCUCGCCUCAGCCGCGCCAGAAACCGCCUUGCCGGACGGCCGCGGGGGUCCCAGCUCCUCAGCUCGCCAUGUCCCGGCUGCUGCCGCUGCUGAGGAGCCGGACCGCGCGCAGCCUGAGGCCGGGCCCGGCCGCCGCCGCCGCGCCCCGCCCGCCGUCCUGGUGCUGCUGCGGGCGGGGGCUGCUGGCGCUCGCGCCCCCCGGCGGCUUGCCGGGCGGCCCCAGGCGGCUGGGCACGCACCCCAAGAAGGAGCCCAUGGAGGCGCUGAACACGGCGCAGGGCGCGCGCGACUUCAUCUACAGCCUGCACUCCACGGAGAGGAGCUGCCUGCUCAAAGAGCUGCACCGCUUCGAGUCUAUUGCCAUUGCCCAAGAAAAAUUGGAAGCUCCACCACCCACCCCAGGACAGCUGAGAUAUGUAUUCAUCCACAAUGCGAUACCUUUCAUAGGGUUUGGCUUUUUGGAUAAUGCAAUUAUGAUUGUUGCUGGAACCCAUAUUGAAAUGUCUAUUGGAAUUAUUUUGGGAAUUUCAACUAUGGCAGCUGCUGCUUUGGGAAAUCUUGUGUCAGAUCUAGCUGGACUUGGACUUGCAGGCUACGUUGAAGCAUUGGCUUCCAGGUUAGGCCUGUCAAUUCCUGAUCUCACACCAAAGCAAGUUGACAUGUGGCAAACACGUCUUAGUACACAUUUGGGCAAAGCUGUUGGGGUGACUAUUGGCUGCAUUCUAGGAAUGUUUCCUUUAAUUUUCUUUGGAGGAGGUGAAGAAGAUGAAAAACUGGAAACGAAAAGUUAAUCCUCUUAGAAUACCUAUAAAAAGAUGUAAACUAAUGUACCUCAGUAAUUAAAUAUGCUGUCACAACAUUUAGGAAUUAAGACAGUAACAGUAUAGAUAUGGGAUCAAAUAAUUUAGCAUGUAUUAUGGAAAACACUAACUUAUUGUGGCUUGAUCUUCUUAGGACAUCUUUUUUAAAAAGCUGUUUAGUAUCAUUUUGUGUAUAUUGUUGAAAUGCUUUUUCAUCAAUAGCAGUCAACAUUUUAUCCUUUCUUUUUAUAUUCAUAAUGUUAUUUAAGUGUCAUUGAUGUACUGUAUUGACUUGGGGUUUGCUUAUUUGUUACUUAACAUGUGUACAUGCAUGAAAGCAUUUUUCGUUGUUCCCUGAUAGUUACAUUUCAACCUUGGGAUUUUUCCAAAUUACUUAAGAUGUUUAAUGUCAGUUAAAGAUUUUUUUACCCUCUUUUUGGGAACAUCAAUUUUGUACUGUUAUGCAGUAAACAUUUAUAAUAAUAUAAUUUCAGUCAUUUCUUAACUGUCACAUCUAUUGAAAAUGGAUAUAGAUACAGGUUUUAAGUAUUUUAAGUAUAUAUUACUUAUUUUAAUUUUCUGACUUUACUAUUUUAAGGGCCAGAGGGUUAAUCACAAAGAGCAAUUAUGUGGUCUCCCUGCUACAUGAAACCGUGUAUACUAACAAGCGUACAAUUUUUAGUUGAUUUUUUUUAACCUUUUAGUUUCCCAGUUUUGAAUAAUUACAUGGUGGAUUCUGACUUUUGAGGGGAAGCAAAUGAUUAUUUUAGAGUCUUUGAAAUGGGGAUUGUGGAAUUAGAUUGAACUAAGGGAUUUAACAUGAUGCUUGGAAAUUAAGAGACUAAAGCUUUUUUUAAAAAAAGGUGGAAAAUAGGAACUGUCAAGAAGGUUUAUGGUAUAAAUGAUGAAGUUGAAGUGAUGUUUGAAAGAUUAAUGAGAUACAAUUUAUAUUAUUUGGUAAGGUUUUUUUUUUUCCCUCCAAAGAUGUCAUCUUCUCAUCUGAAUGGAAUAAGUCUGAAUACCCCAUAUUCAUACUCCUAAUCUCAUUAUAUCUUAUUUAGUGAAUUUUAUUUAUGAAUAAUUUCUGUUGAAGUGAAAACUAGAUAUUUAAUAUUUUGCUUUUUUGCUACAUAGUCUACUCAAAAAUUACAUGAGGAGAAAUCCUUUUUCCCUUUGUUUUUCUUUUUUCUUCUUUUGUGGUAUUUAAAGCAUAUUUUAGGUUGAAGUUACUUAUUUCUAGUCUUGUACUUCUGGCUUAAGUAUAACCAUGUAAGAAUUAUAAAUUUUAGUUUUCUGAACCCUUAAACUUUUUUAGCAUGUGGUCUGUUACACAUGCUAAAAAAUUAGUCUUACUUGUAACAGCGUAAUUAAACACAUCAUGGAGGAGAGAAACUUAAAAUUAAAAUAGUAUUUUGGCUUUUGAAGUUAUUUGUGUUGCUAAAUAGAUGCAGAGGUUUUACAGCAGUUUAUUUUAAGGUUUUAUUUAUACAUAAUUACUUUGAACUCUUCAGAGUAGAUAUUUUUUCACAAGGCAGUUUGUCAUAAAUUCUCUCAUGCGCUUCAGAAUGCAUAAGUGCCAUCCUUUAAUCAUAGACUUUGAGGAGAGAAAGCAUAAAAAUAUAGCAUAUAAUCUAAAAAUAAAUAUAUAACAUGCACAAAUAAUGUGACAUUCUUACUGAAUCAAAUCAUGAUUCUAGAACUUGAGAUCUUAAAUAGAAUUUCGGUUUGUAUCUUCCAUAUAAUAACCACACACAGAUAACCACACAAAAAAUCCUUUGUAAAAUUUCUGAUUGAUAGGAUUAGAGUGCUUAAAUUUUUGGGGGGGGAAGGGUGGGGUAAAGUGUAAGUGCUUUCUUUUGUCCCUAACUUGUGUAUUGAUGGCAGUCCACUCUGUUUUCUAAAAAUGUAUUUUACUGUGGUGCUUAACUUCUUAUUAAUUAAAUCCCGUAUCAGAAACCUUGCCUGUGACUUUAGAAAGGGCUUUUGAUUAUUGUUUUUUCUUCUUGCUCUUGAAAGUAAUCUGGUCCCAGGGAAUUACUGGUUUAACUGAACAUCUCCAGAAUUAUUUAAGGUGUCAAAAUAUAUAACCUUCACAUUGAAAGAUAAUUUUAAUUUAUGGGCAUAAUAAAAAUUUGAAUCAUUCAGGUAAUUUUCAAAAAAUGGAGACCAUUUGUCUUUAACUGAAGGUAUAUGUUUAAGAUCAUAGUCUACCCUAGUAUGGUGCUUUGCCACAAAGUGAUUUCUGAAGAAUGGUUCUUUUUAAGAUAAUGACUUCAUAUGAUCAUUGUUUCAUGUUACUUGCCACAAAUAACUUUAAUUUAGGUUGAAACUGGAACUGUUUGUUUCUCAUAUUAGCUACUUCUCUAUUAGGAGCACAAGAACCAUAGUUAAAUGCAACAUGAGCUACUUUAGUCCUGUUUGUUUAAAUUUGUGUUGUCCAUGUAUUAUGAUUUAUUAACUUGUUGAUGCAUGUAAAUUGGGUGCAUUUUGUUGCCAUGUAUGUUAAAUGGUGACCAAUGUUUUUACAAAGGAAUUGAACAAAAAAAGUAUCUUUUAAGAAAUUUGGAAUGUGGUUUUGAUUUUGAAAUUUGAUUUCUUACUAAUCUCAGAGGGCCUUGGUAUAUUCUGUUACUAAAGCAAACAGGAUUAAUGAAUACGGAUUUGUUACAAGGUGGCAGCAAUGUCACUGAGAUAGUGAAUGGAACAAUUUACCACCUCCCUGGAAUCUGCACCUGAGAUACAACAUCAGCGUAUGAGUGAAGAGUGAGCCCAUAGAAAAGCUUUAGAUAGACUCACAUAAGUCACACUGAUGGGUAUUUACAGCAGAUAUAUCCAAGCUGUUUAUGUAAUAGUCUCAUUUACUUUAUUCUUUUUCUCUAGAACAUAAAUUUUGAAGGUAAUGGAAGUUUAUCUUUUAUACCAAAAGUUUGUAUGAGCCAUUUUGAAGUAAAUCUUUCUAAUUUUAGAAUUAUAUUUUCUCGCCAUCUUAAGACAGUAUAUUAAAUAUAAUAUAACCUUUUUCUUAGUGGCUAAGCAUUAUCUUUAUGUAUAUUAUUAUUGUGUGGUAAUGCAGUACCUUGAGAAUCUAGUUUUUAUAGUUUUCAUUUUUUUUUCUGAUCUUGCUUCUGGCAACUUUUAUCUCUCUAAUCUGCUUUUUUUCUCAGUUGUCUGGACUUAGAAACUGGUUAGCCUAUCUUACCAUAAAUUAUUUGGGAAAUACUAAAAAAUUGGCUUUGGAUCCUGACUGAGAUGAUGAUGAUGAUAGUAGUAGUAGUAAUAAUAAUAGUUCCCUUUUAUUAAACACUUAUUUGGUCCUUUAUGCACUAGUAAUUUACACACAUUAUUGCAUUUAAUCACCUUAAUGACAACAUUAAGUUGGGGCUAUUAUCAUUAUCAUCUCUAUUUUCUCAUAGCUAAAUUGAGGCAUGAAGAGGUUAGUUUGCCACUACGAAUAAGUGGACUGGAAUCCUAUUUUGUCCAAGUAUGAAGCCUGUCUUCUUAACUGCUAGGCAGUAGGGACAUCAGUUGCAUGGGCUUUGCAAUGUCUGCUCUCUGCCUAGGUUCCUUUUUACCUCCAGAUUCAUGGAGUCAUUUUCUUAUCUAUAAUUUAAGAAUAUUGUGCUUACAAUCCAAGAUUCAUUUAAGAAAUCUUGUGUUCUUUAUUACAUACUAUGUGCUAGGAUGUUCAAGGCACUGAGUGAACAACCAGAACAUCUGUACCCUCAUGAAGCUUAUUCUUUUGGGGUGGGUAGUAAUAGGGGAAGAGAACACAGAAAAGCAAAUAUACUUUUUUUUGAGAUGGAGUCUUGAUGUCACCCAGGCUGGAGUGCAGUGGCGUGAUCUUGGCUUAUUGCAACCUCUGCUUCCUGGGUUCAAGUGAUUCUCCUGCCUCAGCCUCCUGAGUAGCUGGGAUUACAGUCACGUGCCACCGAGCCUAAUUUUUUUGUAUUUUUAGUAGAAACGGGGUUUCACCAUGUUGGCCAGGCUGGCCUCAGACUCCUGACCUCCUGAGUAGCUGGGAUUACAGGCACGUGCCACCGAGCCUAAUUUUUUUGUAUUUUUAGUAGAAACGGGGUUUCACCAUGUUGGCCAGGCUGGCCUCAGACUCCUGACCUCAGGUGGUCCACCUGUCUCGGCCUCCCAAAGUGCUGGGAUUACAGGCGUGAGCCCCUGCGCCCACCUGCAAAUAUACACUUAAAUAUUGUUUAUGUCAGAUGGUGGUAAGUUCUAUAGAGAUAAAUGAAACAAGAUAAAGAGGAUAGAAAGUACCAGUGGUCAUAAGUGAAGAUGGUCAGUGAAGACCUGAAGGAAGCGAAGGUACAAACAGUACAGAUAUUCUGUGAAGAGAAAGUAUCAUGCUAGGUACUAGAAAGUUGGUGUUAAGAAAAUCUCAGAUAUGUGAAAUAUGUUUCACUUUGGAAUUCAUUGUAAAAUGUUUUCUUUUUGUUUCAUAUUACUAAUAACUGCAUUAAGCCUAAAGAGUAACAGUUAAAUAUUAAGAUUAAUACUUACUUCUUGCAUGUUUACUGACAGCAGUAGGUGAAAAUGGCACAGAAGUGUGGGGAAGCAACCCUAGAAUUCAAAAAAGUCUGUAGAUAUUCCCAUCAGCAAAUCAUUUACAGUUGACUCUUGAACAAUGGAGGGAUUAGGGACACCAACCCCCUGUGCUGCUGAAAAUCUGAAUACAACUUUUUACUCUCUCCAAACUUUACUUAUAGCCUCCUAUUGGCUGGAAGCCUUUCUGAUAAAUAAGCAGUAGAUUAACACGUAUUUUGUAUGUUAUAUGUAUCAUAUAUUGUAUUAAAAUAAAGGUAGAAGAAAGAAAAUGUUAUUAAAAUCAUCAGGAAGAGAAAAUACAUUUACUAUUCAUUAAGUGGAUCAUGAUAAAAGUCUUCAUCCUCCUUGUCUUCAUGUUGAGUAGGCUGAGGUGGAGGAGGAAGAGGAAGGAUUGGUCUUGCUCUUAGUGGUAGCAGAGGUGCAAGGGGAAGCAGGAAAGGCAGGCACACUACGUGUAAUUAUGAAAAUGCAUUGUAACUUCUGUCUGAUGUUUUGCUUUUUUUCAUUUCUCAAAAUAUUUCUAUAUAUGGUAUUAAUCCUUCUUCCACCAUUUGCUUUAGUUUUAGUGCCUGUGUGAUAGAAGGGUUCAUGUUGUAAAAUCAGUCUUGAAUAAUCAGAACACUUCUACCAGAUUGUCUAAUGUUGAUUUGUUUUCUGGCACUGCUUCUAAAUGUCUUCCUCCUCAUUCUGUGGCACUGAUUCAGAGGCACUCAUCUCCAAAAGCUAAGCUUUUGAAUUGCUUAGCUUUUGAUUCACUCCAGGAUUCAGAUCUUGAAACUUUCUACCCUCCACCAUUUAUUUAUUUAUUUAAUUUGACAUAUCUACAACCUCUUUCAUGAUUUUCUUGAUUGGCUCUGUUGUAAAUUCUGCGAAGUCACACACAACAUCUGGUUGUUUUCCUCAGCAGGAAUUUAUUGUUUUGGGCUUGAUGGCUUUCAUGUCUUCUGUAGCAACAAUGGCAUCAUCAGUGGUGGAAUCCUUCCAGACUUUGAUGAUGUUCUCUUUGUUAGAGUUCUCUUGCAUGGCACUGAUGGUUCUUUGCAUAGAGUACUGUGUGUAAUGAGCCUAUAGGUCCUUAUGACUCCCUGAUCUAGAAACUAAAUUAGAGACAUUGUGUUUGGGGGCAAAUAGAUCACUUCGAUGCCUUUAGUAUUGAACUCAUGGAGUUCUGGGUGGGUGGCCAGGGGCAUUGUCCAGUAUCAAAACAACUUUAAAAGGCAGUCCUUUACUGGCAAGGUACUUCCUGACUUCAAAGACAAAACAGCAAUGGAGCCAAUCCAGAAAAAGGGUUCUUGUCGUCCAGGCCUUCUUGUUAUACUGCCAGAAGACUGGCAGCUGGUGUUUAUCUUUUCCCUUCAAGACUUGGGAGUUAACAGCUUUAUAGAUAAGUGCAGUCUUGAUCAUAAACCCAACAGCAUUUGCAAAAACCCAUAGCAUUAGCCUGUCCCUUUCUGCCUUAAACCCUGGUGCUCACUUCUCUUCUUUACUAAUAAAUGUUCUUUGUGGCAUAUUAUUAUUUUUCCAUAAUAGGGCACUUCUGUCUGCCUUAAGAACCUGUUUUGGUAGAUAUGCUUUCUCCUCAAUGAUUUUCUUAAUGGCAUCUGGGAACUCAUUUGCUGCCUCUUGGUCAUCAGGAGCUGCCUCUUCUGUUAUCUUAACAUUUUUAAAGCCAAACUUCUUUCUAAUAUUAUCAAGCCAUCCUUUGCUGGCAUUAAAUUCUCUAGAUUUAGAUCCUUCACCUUCCUUUUGCUUUAAAUUGUCAUAUAAUGACCGCCUUUUCUCCAAUCAUAUUAGAGCCUAUAGGUACGUCUUUCUUGUAGCAAUACUGCACCCACAUAAAAGUUGCAUUUUUAAUACGAGAUAAAAAGGUAUAUCACAAAAAGUGUAAGGUUUGCUGGUAUAGAUGCAGUAAUGGCUUCAUAAAUUUUCUUAAUUUUUUUUAACAGUGGUCCUUAUGCUGGAUUCAUUUAUCUUGAAGGAUGGGCAACUACAGCUGCAGACCAGUACACAUCAAGCAAUUUAACUUUUUCUUGUAAUGUCAUGACUUUGCUCCUUGGGAGCACUUCCAGCGUCACUAGCGGGACUUCAUAUGGGUCCCUUGGUAUUAUUGCAAGGUUUAUGGUUGUACUAAACAUGAUGAAAAAUAACUGAGAACCAUGAGAGAUCACUUUUUACUACGAUACACAAUUUACUGGAGAGAUGAACUGCCCAUGUGGAGAUGAUAAACAUCACAUGGCAUUUUAAGUGAAUACAGCACUUGAGCUCACAGCAACAGCAACAGGAGGUAGCUCUGAAAUUAUGGUAGUAGUGCAGUAUGUACUAUAGUUAAUCUUAUCCAGUUGUAAUUUAGUACUGCAUCUUUAUGUUUGUCUCAACUGCAAAUGGCUCCAAUGUAUAGUCUGUGUAUGCGUUAAGUUUUGAUAAAUUUUAACUUUUUUUUUUUUUGAGAUGGAGUCUUGCUCUGUUGUCCAGGCUGGAGUGCAGUGGCACCAUGCCGGCUCACUGCAACCUCUGUCUUCUGGGUUCAAGUGAUUCUCCUGCCUCAGCCUCCCAAGUAGUUGGGAUUACAGGCAUGCAUCCCCAUGCCCAGCUAAUUUUUGUAUUUUUAGGAGAAACAGGGUUUCACCAUGUUGGCCAGGCUGCUCUUGAACUCCUGACCUCAGGUGAUCCGCCUGCCUCGGCCUCCUGAAGUGUUGGGAUUACAGGCGUGAGCCACUGCGCCCGGCCAAUUUUAACUUUUCAUAAUAGAUUUGUAUAUAUUUAUGGUAGUAAAUGAUAAAAUAGACUAGUGUCUACAUAUAUUAUAUGAAUUCAUGACACACCUUUUUCUUAGUUUUUCAGUAUUUCUAAGCUACAUGGUGCAUCUGCAAGUUUUUUAAAUUGUUGCAAAUUUCCAAAAAAAUUUUCAAUAUAUUUAUCAAAAUAUGCAUAUAAGCGGUCCUAUGCAGUUCAAACCCGUGUUUGAGAAUCAACUUUAUGACUUCCAGUGUCAUUCUCCACCAUUUCUGCAGUUUAUCACAUUUUGCUUCAGGCAGAUUUGGUAAAUCUUCAAUGAUAGUUCUCUAGGCCAUUGUUUUGUAACAUGAUCAAAUGCUUAAUGGGAAAUAGAAUAUGUAUAUGUAUUCUUUGUCUACCAACUACCAAAGAAACAAAUACUCCUCAGUUUGACUUGACUUAGUAAAUAAACUUGUGUUGGGUUAAUGGA